GCUAUGCACAGUGUUUUCAUGUGGGCCAUGUUAUAAGCCCCACAGAAGCCCUAUCAGGAAAUAUUUCUUUAAGGACUCAUCAAACUGUGUGCAAACAAGGUCUGUUUCCAUCUCUCCCCCUUUUAUCAUGACAUCACUAGAAAGCAGUUUAUAGUAGUAAUGUCUUUGGAGAAAAUAAUAAACUACGAAGUCUCUUCCAUCUAGGUGCUUUCAUUAUCUGUAUCUGGGCAGGCCCUGACUAGAGAAAAAAAAGAAAUUAUAUUCAAGGACAAAAUAGAGACCAGUGUUUGGGCUGGGAAGAACAGAGAUUUUAUUCUUUAAUUUUGAAGGUUGAUCAUUUGUUACUUUAUGAAAAACCUUGUAGCCAUUUUUAAAUAGUAUCUGAUCUUGGUCUUUCCCCCUAAAAAAGGCAAGAAAGGUUAAAUUCAAAGCUACCUGCACAAAUUUCAGACCCAUUUUGCCUGAGCUUUUUUGCAUUUGUGAAGAAGUGAUCAGACUUGACAGUAGAGUUGUUGGGAGAGUUUGAAAGUAUGAUAUGGGUAUGGGGUGAAAUUGAUUUCCAGCUUAAUUAAAUCUAUUGUGAACUUGUUAGUGAAGCAAAUCUACAUGUUAAUUGUUGUAAAGGAGUUCCCCUCAACUCACUUCCAUGGGGCUUUGUGUUAUUCUCACCGCCCCCUCCCCUGCCUACCAUUCCAGUUGCUUACCCACUCAUCCUCAGCAUGGCAGGCUCGGCCAUUCCUCAACAAUGACGUUAUUUGUCCUUUUAAAAUAUUCCGAUCGCUCAUAUUUGCUCUCUGUUUCGGACAGCAGUGGAAGGCAUUUCAGGAAAAAAAACUGUGUUACUCAAAAUAAACAUGAAGAUAAUAUUGAGAGGAGUGAAAUGAAAUAAAUUUGCUAGACGGAAAAAGAGAAAAAUCCAAAGGAAGGAAUGGAAGGCACAAACCCAGUAACAUGGUGGCGUGGGUGCUAUCUCCAGGUGAACAAGACAGAACUUGCAGGCAACAUGGAAUCUCAUCUCCCAUCCCACUCACGUCCUUUCCACUCGGCCCUGCAUUCUCUUCUGCAGGUUUGAGAUGGCCCACAUAGCCAAUGUAGAGCUCUUCAGGAGAUAUUUUUACAGAAAAUCCUGAUCACAUGGCCUCCAUUUGUUUAUUCUCUUGCCGUUUUUGUUUUUUUUUUUAACUUUUUUUUUUUUUAAGACAGAGUUUCACUUUGUCGCCCAGGCUGGAAUGCAAUGGCACAAUCUGGGCUCACUGCAACCUCCGCCUCCUGGGUUCAAGCGAUUCUCAUGCCUCAGCCUCCCAAGUAGCUAGGAUUACAGGCACCCAUCACCAUGCCCAGCUAAUUUUUGUAUUUUUAGUAGAGAUGGGGUUUCACAAUAUUGGCCAGGCUGGUCUCAAACUCCUGACCUAAGAUGAUCCACCUGCCUUGGCCUCCUAAAGUGCUGGGAUUACAGGCAUGGGCCACUGUGCUCAGCCUAUUUUUUACUUUUUUUAGAGAUGGGGUCUUGCUGUGUUACCCAGGCUGGAGUGUAGUGGCAUGAUCAUAGCUCACUACAGCCUUGAACUCCUCUUGCCAUUUUUUUUAUCCUUAAAAUUUCCAUGUCUCACUCUCUUGCCAACUGUUCUCUCUCAUUUGGUCCCUUGAUUCACUCUAAACUCAAACCCUGAUAAAGCAGCUGAUCGGUGAAGUGUCUGUUGUUACUAAAGUAGAAGUUAGAGGCAGAACAGUGGCAGAGAGCCCUGGAAUCUGGCCCUUGGUAGGUGCUCCACAAAUGUUUGUUGAACAAAUGAAUAAGUGGAGCCAGGUUGUCUAUGCCCUAGUCCCAGCUCUCUCACAUGCGCUAGUGAGAGAUAUAUACAUGUAUAAAAAAAAAUCUCCCUGUGCCUCAGUUUCCUCAUCUGUAAAAUGGGGAAGAUCAUUAUAGGCUUGUAAAUGAAAUGAAUUAAUACUUAUAAAAUGCUUAAAUUAGUCCUGGAUCAAAGUAAGCUUUCAAUAAAUUGUAAGCUCUUAUGUUCAAGCUCUCAGAACCAGAAUACUCGAGAUGCAGACAAAACAUUACCUCUCUUAAGAGGUUUGUUGGGGAAAGUAUAGCUGGAGUUAAAAAUUUAACCUCUUAGAUAAGUCACUGUUCAAGCUACUGGUUUUCAUCUCCACCAUUCCACCUAAAUUGCCACCACCUUGCUGAAUUAGACACACUUGACCACCCUUCCUUCUUGGCCUAGUGUUUUUCUGGGAUUGUCCGUAACACCAAAUAUUUCUCUAAACUCACUAAACAUCUCUUUUUAAUUCCCAUUGCAAAAUCCUUUUUGUUUACCUGUACUUAUUUUUUAACUUUCAUUUUGAAAUAAUUAUAAGUUCACAAGAAAUUACAAUAAUAAUAUACUGGGAGGACCCAAGUGUCUAGUGUCCUUCAGUGGUAACAUCUUGCAUAGCUAUAGUUCAGUAUCAAAACCAGGAAAAAUGCAUUGGGAAAACUGCAGAGCUUAUUAAGAUGUCAUCAGUUUUAUUUGUACGUGUGUGUGUGUGUGUGUGUGUGUGUGUGUGUGUAUGCGUGCCUAUGCAAUUUUGUCAUGUUUAGCUUUGUAUAACCACCACUGGAACUGUUUCACUACCACAUGGCUCCCUUGUGCUACCUCUUUAUAGCUGCAGCUUCUAAUCUGUUCUCUGUCUAUAAUUUUAUAAUUCAAAAAUGCUAUGUACAUGAAUCUGUAACCAUUUGGCUUGGCUUUCUCCAUUCAGCAUGAUUCCCAUGAGAUCCAUCCAAGUUGUUGAGAUUAUCGAUAGUUCAUUCCUUGUUAUUGCUGCAUUGUGUCCCAUGGUACAGGUGUACCAUAGUUUGUUUAGCAGUUCACCCACUGAAGGGCAUUUGAGUUGUUUCCAGUUUUUGGCUAUUACAAAUAAAGCUGUUAUGAAUAUUUGUGCACACAGACAUACAUUGUGUGAGCAUAGGUUUUCAUUUCUCUGGGAUAAAUGCCCAAGAGUGGAAUUGUUGGGUCAUAAGUUAAAUGCAUGUUUAGCUUUUUAAGAAACUGCCAAACUAUUUUCCAGUGUGGCUGUACCAUUUUAUAUUCCGACCAGCAGUAUAUGAGUAAUAUCACUUCUCCACAGCCUUGCCAGCAUUUGAUGUUGUUUUUACGUUUCACUUUAGUCAUGCUGAUGGGUGUGUAGUGAUACCUCAUUGUGGUUUUAGUUGACAUUUCUCUACCGGCUAAUGAUGUGAAAACAUCUUUUCGUGUACUUAUUUGCUAUGUGUGUUAUCUUCUUUGGUGAAAUGUCUGUCUUUUGCCUUCUCAUAUAGUUUGGAUAUUUGUCGCCUCCAAAUUUCAUGUUGAAAUUGAAUCCCUGGUAUUAGUAGCAGGGCCUGGUGGGAAGUUUGGAUCAUGGGGAGGAUACCUCAUAAAUCAUUUUUAUAGUGGCAAGUUCUCACUAUAUUAUUAUCAUGAGAAUAUACCAUCCCCUCCUUUCUUUCUUCUUCUCUUACCAUGUGAUGCCUGCUCCCAUUGCCUUCUGCCAUGAGUGGAAGCUUCCUGAGGCCCUCACUGGAAGCAGAUGCUGAUACCAUACUUCUUGUACAGUCUGGAGAACUUUCUGGAGGCCAGAAGUCUGAAAUUUUAGUGAGCCCCAAUCAAAGUUUUGGCAGGGCCGAAUAACUUCUGGAAGCCUGCCUUUUCCAGGCCAAAGAAGCCCUCGAAAAUACUGAAGUUCCUGUUGGCUGUCUUAUGGUCUACAACAAUGAAGUUGUAGGGAAGGGGAGAAAUGAAGUUAACCAAACCAAAAAUGCUACUCGACAUGCAGAAAUGGUGGCCAUCGAUCAGGUCCUCGAUUGGUGUCGUCAAAGUGGCAAGAGUCCCUCUGAAGUAUUUGAACACACUGUGUUGUAUGUCACUGUGGAGCCGUGCAUUAUGUGUGCAGCUGCUCUCCGCCUGAUGAAAAUCCCGCUGGUUGUAUAUGGCUGUCAGAAUGAACGAUUUGGUGGUUGUGGCUCUGUUCUAAAUAUUGCCUCUGCUGACCUACCAAACACUGGGAGACCAUUUCAGUGUAUCCCUGGAUAUCGGGCUGAGGAAGCAGUGGAAAUGUUAAAGACCUUCUACAAACAAGAAAAUCCAAAUGCACCAAAAUCGAAAGUUCGGAAAAAGGAAUGUCAGAAAUCUUGAACAUGUUCUGAUGAAAGAACCAAGUGACCCAAAGUGACCUGGACAAGAUUCAUAGACUGAAAGCUGUUGACAUCGUUGAAUCAUAUGUUUAUAUAUUGUUUUUAAUCUGCAGGAAAAUGGUGUCUCUCAUCAUUUGCUCUGUUAAGGGAACAAAUUAGCACUUUUUAGAAGUCUGACAAUUGUAAACAGUUAUUAGCUUUUCCAGAAGCUGAUUCCCAUUUUAAGAUGGGGGAAAAUUAAGGUUUGAGGUUUUAGAAAUUAGCAAGUAGUGCAUACCCUUCUAGCCACAAGUGCCCAGUCCAGGCAAGUGCUGACUUCUUAGAGAAUGUGUGGCCAGACCCAGGGACCUGGAGUGUGUUUGGACUGCAGUUUGCCACCCUGAGAACACCUUCUCCAGGACUGGCAUUUCAGAAUCAGAUUCUUCAUUUUUUGCAGCUACGAUGUUCUUCCAGGGCACUGGGGGCUGUGACUUCUCUCUAAAUUGUAUAUAAGUUGUGUAUAUAGAGACCAUAAUUAUAUGGUCCUUAGAAAAGACUUUGCUUUUAUAAAGCAUUUAGAAAAAAUGCAUACUUUUAAAACAAGUGCUUGAGUUGUCACUUAAAAAUUAUAGCAUAUUGCUAUAAUAAAACCUUAUUUAUGUCUUAUUUGAAGAUGAAUAGUCUUAAAAGAUAAAGACAUAAAUGGGACAAUUGUUAUUGAGCAAAAAACCAAAUUAUCCCACCCUCAUGGAGCUUAUAUUCUAGCAAGGGGAGAUGGAUAUGAUAGAUUACACAGUUUAUUGGAGGACAAUAAGAGUUAUGGCAAAAAGCAAAAGGAACACAGGGUAAAGGGGAUAGGUGCCAUUUGGUGGUGAGAAUGCUGACUGAAAAAUAGAAUGAUCAAUUUAAUCUGAAACAAAUGGUUAUUUCUUUUAUAAUCCAUAUAAUAAAUUUAAAAUCUAAAAUGUAAAAUUUUGAACACAACACUGGAAAGGGUAUCCACAGCAGGAAGUCCCCAGUUCACCUCCAUGACUACAGGGCAGCUUUGCACAGCCCUCUGGGCGCACUGUGUGCCUCUGCCCAGAAGGGGGCCUCGCCGUUCCACCAGAAGCUCAGCUCCAGGCCCUGGAGGGGCUGCUGCUCCUCAGUUGCAUUUCUUCAGUAGAUUCAUUUCCUUGAUGCAAAGCAUCUGUAUUUGUUGGUUCUGUCAUUUGAGCGAUGUCUCUGACUUGUUUGUUUUGAAUUACAUUACAGGCUGGAAUGUAAUUGUGGUGAAAGUAUUUUUAUAUUGCUGAGAGUAGCAGCUAAUCACAGUUACAUGCUUCAGAGGACUUAUAAUUGCUUGGUUUUGUGUGUGUGUGUGUGUGUGUGUGUGUGUGUGUGUGUGUUUAACUGCAUUUGAAAAGUUUUAUGGAGAAUAUGCAUGAUUUUAAAUCUGUGAUAAUGUUACAUGCACCUUCAAUUUCAUCCACUUUAAAAAUUAUCUUCUCAUUGAAUUUUAGUGCUUCUACUAGUUUGUUCCUUUUUGCAGUUGGUCGUAAUUCAUUUCUGGCUUCUUAUGCUUUCCUGCAAGCAGAUUUCAUUGCAUUUAUUGUGUUCAUAUCAUUUUCUUGGGGAUUAUUUGUAGGACAACCAACCUGGAGUUUUGCCUCUCUAGAGUACCACCCAGUAAGUCUGGCUGAGCAUCUUAUGUCCAGUAGGUUCUUGGUAAACAUUUGCUAAAUGAAAUUACUGAUUGAAAUUUGGGGAAAAGUGAAUAAGAAGACUAUCUAGGACAAAAAGCCAAAGCCGAAAAUAGUAUAUGAGCAUUCUAGCCCAGAGACUGUCGCUACUAAAAGAAUGAAGGAAAUAAUAAAGUGAUAGACAGGGAAGGAUAGAAAAGACUUAACAAUAUACAUAUGUUCCGUCUUUGCUGUUUUGGAGAAUGAUGGAUAAGUAGUGUUUCCUGAUUCUGAAGCAUAGCUGAACAAUUUAAUUGUGGUUUACCAUCUUUUUGGUUCCCUCUUCAGUAAUUAACCUAUCGAAAAUCUGUCCUAAAUGUUUGGACUGGGGCACAGUUCCCUCCAUCGCUUUGGGAGAAAAUCAUUAAUAUGGCAUACUGCAGAUUGGAGGGCAGGACCACUGAGGGUGUCAUAGACAUUAGCUCUAUGGAAUUCUGCUAGCAAUUUCCAAGUGACAGUGAGGAAUUAUGGAUAUAUGUUGAGGUCAUUCAGCUUCCUGAGUACCACAUUCCCCAGCUACUUAGACACGGGUUAAAAUAUUAAGAUGUCCUAGUUCAACAGCUUGAAUUCCAUUGAUUGAUACUGAUAGUGCCUGUCCAAGACACCAGCUGAAAGACUUGUUUUGUGUACAAAAUAGUUCUGAAAGUGGUGAGAUACAAAAAGGUUUUAGAAUCACUGCCCUGUUGAGAGAAAUUAGGGGGAAAUGAUUACAUUUAGAAGCUGCUAGAGUUAUCCAGUGUUUGCUGGUCUUUGCAACAAACUGUGGAGAAUGGGUGGUAUGUAAUGCUUUGGUAGGCUUCAAUCACUGAUAAAAGAUCAUGUUAAAAUAUCUUUGUGCUUUCUUGUUACUUGGCACAACCAUCUCUUCCUGUGUUGUAUUUGGAGUAUCAUGGAGAGAAAAUAGAUGGCCAAGAGCUUCAGUGUAGGCAAGAACUCUUAAUUUUUCUUUAAACUUUUUACUGGGAAAAGUAUAUAUAUAUAAAAUACACACACACACACACACACACACACACACACACACACACACACAAACACAACACACCAUGGCCCUUUACCCCGAAAUGCUUCAGUAUAGUUAUUGACUUAAGUAAAUUUAACAUUGAUAUACUUGAAUCUAUCAUUUGUAUUACAGUUUUGUCAGCUGACCCAAUAAUGUCCUGUAAAGAAGUUCUCCCACUACCCUAUAAUCCCAGGUCCAGUCUAGGGUCCAGCAUUACAUUUACUUGUCUUGAAUCCAGCUUUUUCUUUUUUUUUUUUUUUUUUGAGAUAGGUCUCACUCUGUCGUCCAGUGGCAUGAUCACAGCUCACUGCAGCCUCAACCUGGCUCAAGCAAUCCUUCCUCCUCAGCCUCCUGAGUAGCUGGGACCACAGACUCAUGUCACCACACCUAAUUUUUUUUUUUUUUUUUUUUUGUAGAGACAAGGUCUCACUAUGUUGCCCAGGCUGGUCUUGAACUCCUAGGCUGAAGCAAUCCUCCUUCCUUGGCCUCCCAAAGCACUGGGAUUAUAGACGUGAGCCACUGCACCGGUCUGCCUUUAGCUUCUUUUAGUCUAGAACAUUUUCACUGGCUUUCUUUGUCUUUUAUGACAUUGACAUUUUUAAAUAAUACAGUCAUUUUGCCUCCUUUCUGUUUUCUUCUUCUUUUUUUAAAUAAUAGAAUGGUCCUUGUUUUAAAUUUAUUUGAUAUUUUCUUGUGAUUAGAUUCAGGUGCUGGUUGAUGUUAAGUUCCUCACAGGAUAUCACAUCUGGAGGCACACAAAGGCCGUCACACCAAGGUGAUGUCAAUUUUGGUCAUCUGGUCAAGGUGUUGUCCUAUUCCUUCACUAUAUAGUUACCUUUUUUCUCUGUUGCAAUGAAUAAGCAGUCUGUGGGAAGAGGAGCUGUUACAUUUUAAACAGAAAAUGUAUUUGACACUGAUGGAAAGGAGAGGAGGAAAAUUAAUGACAUAAAUUUCAAAGCAACUAUUAAAUUAUUUGAUUGCAUUCUUCCUCUUUUACUGUCUGCCAAAAUUGAUAAAAAAAAUUUUUCUAAUAAGAAUGUUUUAAAUAGUGAUAUCUUAAUAAGCAUCAAAAUUAAGCCUGAGAAAUAAAUUCUUUCCUUCCUAAUUUCCUCCUCAGCAAAAGUAAUAAUUAUAUAAAUUUCAUUAUGCCUGAUAAGAUAGGGUUUUGGAAAAUAGACCUAAGAUGUUUCUGAUACUGCAGAUGACCUAUGGUGAUCCAAUGGGAUAAACACUCUAGGUAGGUUGUCAUUUGGUCAUAAAAUAUGAGUUAUCUUGGGUUUCCAUAGAGACAUCUAGACUUAAAAUGUUGUAAGCACUGCUACUUUCAAAAUGUCAGUAAAAAUAGCAAAAGCCAAAGCUCUUGAAAAAAUUACUUAAAUCUUUUUUAAAAGUAGUAUAGCGCCUUGUUAAAAAUCUGUGGUGAUGCCAAAGCUUGUCUUUCCCAGUGGUCCUACGUGAACUGGCCUUAUAGCCCCAGGGAAACCAGACACCAGGAAUUGGUUUCUCUGCCUUUUGGCAAAGGAAUAAGACUACAUUGACUUCAUCUAUGAAGACAACUGCCAACUAUUUCCUUUGUAAAUUGCUAAUUUUGUGUAGUGAGGAAAGGAGCGAUGGGCGACGUGAUUUUUAUGGAUUAGACUGGUGAGUUCUGCUGAAAGUUUGACAUCUUUAGGAUCUUACAUUUUCUUCAAGUUGAGCUAAUGAAAACAGGCUCGUGACUAUUUAUCACCUGAUUUCUAAGUGGAUAUUGGGUUGAACACCACAUAUCCAUGACUAUUAAGGAGGCUUCAUGGUGUAGUUUGACAAAGGCUCUCUCCUUGACCAAACUUCAGUCAGGCCCUAAGUCCUCUUUUUAACCAGGCCUCCACCUUGGCCCCCAUUCUUGAUGGGCCUAUACAGCCCAGCUUUAGCAAGAAUCCUGCUAAGCUAGUUUAGAGAGAAUCCCACAUCCCCAAUAUCUAUGAAAUUUCUCAUCCCCUACUUUUGAUGUGUAAGUCCUUGGCCUCCCUUCAACGAGAAGCCUGUUAAGUUCAUUUUGCAAGAACUCUACUCUUGAUAUCUCCUCUUAGUAAUUUCCUAAUCACUGACCCCCUCACUCUGCCCAUUAGUUAUAAACCCCCACAUGUUCUGGUUGUAUUCAGAGCUGAGCCUGAUCUCUUCCUCUUGUUGGGAUAGUUUUAAAACCUGCGAUAGUUUUAAAACCUAUCACUGUAGUCCUGAAUUAAGUCUUCCUUACCUUAACAAGUGUCAAAAUAAAUUUUUCUUUAACAUGUUGAAGCAUGAACUUGAGAAUCUAGAGCAGGAGUCCACAAAGUAUGGCCCAUGGGCCAUAUCCAGCCCGCUGCCGGUUUCGGUACCACUCAUGACUUAAAAAUGGGUCUUACAAUUCUGAGUGAUUGAAAAAAAAUCAAAAGAAGGAUAAUAUUUAGUGACCCAUGAACCUUAUAUGGCAAUCAAAUUUCAGUGUCCAUAAAUAAAGUUACAUUGGAUGACAGCCAUGCCCAUUUGUUUCUGUGUUGUCUGUGGCUGCUCGUGUGCUACAAUGGCAGAGUUGAGCAGUGGUGACAAACCAUGCGACUCACAAAGGCCUAAAAUAUUUAGCGUCUGGCCCUUCGAGAAAAUGUUAGCUGCCCCUGGUCUAGAGUAGGUAAAAGGCUGAGAUUGGAAGCUGCUUGUUCAAAUUCUGUGAUUGGAACCGAAUGAUGUGGCUCAUUGUACAGCUCAUGGUGAAUUGCUUCAGUACCAUGGUUUUGUUUUUUCCUUUUGAAAAGUUGGUCUAUAAAUGUAAAGGAAAAAUCUAAGAUACCAAAAUAUGUUUUCUGGCUUAGAAUGUUUUAUUUCCUUGUAUACAUUUUAAGAGAGUGGCAAGGAGAAAAGAUAAUGUAUCAUUUUAUUUGGGUUUAGAAUAAAUAAUACAUUUUAUUUAUGAUCA